AUCUUGGACCAGCCCGAGGAAGAUACUGAGGGAGCACAGGAGCAGUCACCGCUGCCACUGCUACUGCCGCUACUGCUGCCGGCGCGUCUGCACCUCUCGGCCUGCCAGUGUACCUGCCGGCGCCUCGGUCGACCGCCCCCGCCCCCUCUCCCGCUGCGUCCGCACUCCUGUUCCUGGUCCUGACGCCCCCCUCCCGCCCGGAAAGCUGCCCAGCCACCAGCAACCCCCCAGUGCCACCAUGGCAACUGCACCAUACAACUACUCUUACAUCUUUAAAUAUAUUAUUAUUGGGGACAUGGGAGUAGGAAAAUCUUGCUUGCUUCAUCAAUUUACAGAAAAAAAAUUUAUGGCUGAUUGUCCUCACACAAUUGGUGUUGAAUUUGGUACAAGAAUAAUCGAAGUUAGUGGCCAAAAAAUAAAACUGCAGAUUUGGGAUACGGCAGGACAGGAGCGAUUUAGGGCUGUUACACGGAGCUACUACAGAGGAGCUGCGGGAGCUCUUAUGGUCUAUGAUAUCACUAGAAGAAGUACAUAUAACCACUUAAGCAGCUGGUUGACAGAUGCAAGGAAUCUCACCAAUCCAAAUACUGUAAUAAUUCUCAUAGGAAAUAAAGCAGAUUUGGAGGCACAGAGAGAUGUUACAUAUGAAGAAGCCAAACAGUUUGCUGAAGAAAAUGGCUUAUUGUUCCUCGAAGCGAGUGCAAAAACGGGAGAGAAUGUAGAAGAUGCCUUCCUUGAGGCUGCCAAGAAAAUCUAUCAGAACAUUCAGGAUGGAAGCUUGGAUCUGAAUGCUGCUGAGUCUGGUGUACAACACAAACCUUCAGCCCCGCAGGGAGGCCGGCUAACCAGUGAACCCCAACCCCAGAGAGAAGGCUGUGGCUGCUAGUGACCUCUUUGCUGUGGCCCCUCAUUUGACCUUUCACCUCUGUCUGUUGGAAGCAGUACUUUUUACUGCCUCAUUGUCUUCUGUACAUCUUACUGGGUUUAAUUAAAAAAAAAGAAAAAACUCUGUUGUAAAAACAGUUUAACACAAUACUAAACUGCUAAACAACUAGAUGUAAUCAGGUUAUCAAAGGCAAGUAGAGUAAUAAAUCUCUCCUGCAUGGUAAAUCUAGACUUUUUUUCCCCCUUGUCCUCGUGAUAAGUAUGUCACCAAUAUAUGAUUUAAACCGAGCACUGAUGCUGGACUUCAUGAUUUUUACCCUCCCUUUGGCAAGGCUUUGUCUCACUGUACGGUUUAAUUUGGUGAUAUCUUAAGCCUUUCUUCCCAUCCUUAACUGUUCAAGUAUGUCUGUUGUAACCAAUAAGUUUAUUGCUGUGAAAUUACUUCUGAUGGUAGAGAAGGGGUUCUAUAACUGCUUUUGUUUUGUUUUGGAUAAAUUUCCUGUUGUGUGGGUGGCAUUUUUCUUAACGAGAUUUGCUUCUGUCUUAGCCUCACACAGGGAAAAUAUCCAUUUAUCUUCUCUCUCGUGCUUAAUUAAUAGCUUUAUCUUUUUUUAUACCAUUUUAUCCUUUUCUCUUUAACAGAAAGUAAAUAUGUAUAAAAUUUGAAGGAAUCGAACUAACAAUACAUUCUGUGUAUAUUAUUUUAAUGAAGAAAAUAAAUUGAUUACUGGCAUUGGAACAGUAUAAAAUACCAGUUUGUACAGUAUGACCUAUAUGUGACCAUGUUACUCCCUUCCAUUUCACACAAAGAAAUAGACACAACUGCAGUUCACAAGUAGUACUGGCUCCACCCCUUGGUGCUGGCAGUGUUUGGGGACAUUAUGCUGGAAAGAGCUCCUAGCAUCAGAGGAUUAACACUAGCAGAUUCUGUUCCAUCUUUGCACUGUUGCUUACCUGCUGAUUUUCUUAACUGUUCUUGUGCAAUCGACAAUGUGCUAACCUGCUUUUCUCUUUUUGUAAACGUUUUUGCAUUACAGGCUGCAUUCUUGCCUUACUGUAUAGAAAAAGAAAAAAGGCUGGGUUUACUAUUGCACAUUUUAAGCUUUUAUACCUUUAUCUUCUUGGAAUGGUCAGAUUCUGAACUGGACAGUCAGAACCACAGGUCUGCUGUUAAGGGAUUUUAAAUUGUGCAUUUUUAACCCUACAGUGAAAUAACUUAAGAUAUCCCUGUGUUCACAGUGUGAGGGGCUGUUUUAUGUCAUGUUGGCAUAAAUUGUUUUGUAAAAGGGAAAGUGUUUCUAAAGGUGUUUCAGCGCUUGUGCUGAUACAAAGUAAGUUAUUACUUUGCACCAGGUGGUUUGGCCACUGAAUUAAUACUGUAUAGCAAGAGAAACAAUCUUAUUUUUUUGGACAACAUGUUUUAUUAAGUUCUUCAUUUCUGUUGAUUUUUUUUAUUGCAUUUAUGAUUCAGUGGCUGGGAAUUGAGAAUUUAUUUGAAAUAGAAUAGGUAACACCUCAGCGUACUAUAGAAAAUGCACUCAGCUCAACUGCUGUGUUUAAAAUACACAUUUUAAAUCCCUCUUUACAGACACUAACAUAAAAGUACAUCUUUCUGGGUUGUAAACAUGUGGUAGUACCAGAGUAUUGUAUAGUCAAUGUUAAAUAAAAGCCAAAACUGGAAUGUGCAGAAAGUAGGCUUUGGUUAAUUUGUGGAUUCAUUUUUAUUUUUGUCUUUGUUUAACUUUUUAAAAAAUAAGAUUUCUGGAGUAGAUUGGUAUAUUCUGUUAAAGACUUACAGUGAUCCAUUUUGCUUACACUGUUGCAUCACAAGGGACUCACCCAGGGACCAUGACCUGCUGGUGUGUGUGUAUAUUUACAAAAACAAAACAAACAAACCACCCAUUGGGAUAUAAGGUAGCAAUCACAAACUAAAGACUGCGGCUUGUUGAGGUGCAAUACCCUGACUCCCAAAGUUAGUUACAGUGGGUUUUAUUGUUUUUGUGACUGAAGGAUUUAUUCAGACUGCUGUACUCUUCAUUUGAUGUAACAAAAUGCUAUUAAUCUAAAUAUUUGUAAAUAAAGUACCUGUAUCUAGAUUAAAUUAAAAUUGGUUGCAUUAUUUUCUGAACUAUAAUAGGGUUUUUCUUCAGGUGAACAAUUUGACGUGUCAUCAGUUUUUAUUGCAGCACUGUCCAUAUUCAUUGUAUAAAGAGAGGUCUACGUAUGUAGCAUAUAAAACCACAUCACUAAGUAAUAGACCCACAGCUUUAUUCUUGUGUUUACAUUACCCUUGAAAUGUUUUCAGUCAACCCUUUUCAGUGUAAGAUCAGCACAUUUGGUGGCUGAUGCUGUUCUCCUUUGACUGUACCGGGAGCCAGAUUCUAUCAUAUGCAUGUGUAAUCCCCUGUAAUACACUCAGGUGCUCACAAAUAGAGCAGAUUGUCAUAUUGUAACAUGCGUGUGCCAGACACCGGGCAGUACACUUUGGAAAGAAUGUGAAAUCCUUUUAAUUUUUAAUCCAUAGCUUACUGCUUGUGCAGUCACCUGCCUCUUGAGGUUGCUCAUUGCCCUUGGACCUGUGAGGAGGCCUUCAGAUUAGUAAUUGGUGCUUAGUACUAUUUAUGCUUAAAUAGAUCUUCCAGUACAAUGUUGAAGUCUUUUUUAUGGAUAAUAACGUGUUUGAUGGAGUAACUUAUUAUUUUUUUUUGGUUGGUGGUUUACACGUUAAUAGAGGUAGUACAAUUUCUUUGGAAAGGUGUCUUUUGAAGCCAGCUGUUAAGCUUCAUACAUUACCUCCCUUCUCAAAUUCGGUAAGACAGUAGUUUUGGGGAACUUUUUUGCCCAUGUGUCUUUUAAGUGUGAUUUUAAAAAAAUGAGUGGUUCAGUUCAUUCCCCUAAACAGAAGAAAAGACCAAAUAAUUACCUUCCAUUCCUCUUCAUGUGGGAAUAUAGAGAGGGUUCAUGUGGCAUUUUAGAGAAAAGAUAAUUUAUCCUCAUUCAACACAGGCCCAGAAAAUUGUGUCCCAGAAGGAUGUCAGUAAUUGUGACUAGGCCAGGCCUUUUAGCAUUUUGCUAAGACUUGAAACAAAAAAUGUAAAUACAAAAGAAAUCAAGUUUUGUUUUGAAAGAUGCCUUCUAGAACUUACUGUGUAUUAAUAAAUUGUCACUUUCAUUGUCUUUAUUGUAACUCCAUUGAUCCCGUAUCUUAACGGUUCACGUCUAGCCAAAUAACUGUUUUGGAAUAAAAACCUUGGUGGUGAGGGA